ACGUGACAUGGGUUGGAAGAUGGCGUCUCCCACAGACGGGACAGAUCUGGAAGCAUCUUUGCUAAGUUUUGAAAAACUUGACCGUGCCUCACCAGAUCUUUGGCCAGAACAAUUACCAGGUGUUGCUGAAUUUGCAGCUUCCUUCAAAAGUCCUAUUACUAGUUCUCCACCCAAAUGGAUGGCUGAGAUAGAACGUGAUGACAUCGACAUGUUGAAAGAACUGGGGAGUCUCACCACGGCUAAUUUGAUGGAGAAGGUUCGAGGCCUACAGAACCUAGCCUAUCAGCUGGGGCUGGAUGAGUGGUCUCCCUCUGUCACCCAGGCUGGAGUGCAAUGGUGUGAUCUUGGCUCACUGCAACCCCUACCUCCCGGGCUCAAGCAAGUCCCCCACCUCAGCUUCCCAAGUAGCUGGGACUACAGGUGUGAGCCACAGCGCCCGGCCAGAAAUGCUUUUUUAAUAUAACUGAGAUUAGUGUGUGUGUGUGUGUGUGUGUGUGUGUGUGUGUGUGUAGUUUUAACUUGUGCUUUAAAAAAUUUUAUUCUAUCUUAAGCAUUUUCCUGUGUCAUUAAAAGUUCUACCACUGAAGAUUUUUGAAUAGGAAAGAUACACACCUUUAGGAGGCAUUGGUGCACAGGAUAGAGUAGGAUGGUAGAGAGAGGAGGCAGGAAGUUACAGUGGGAAUCCAGGGUGAAGGAUUGAGAGCUUGAAUGGAUGAUGGCAGUGAGAAUGGGAAGAAGUGCACUGACAAUAGAUUUUUCAGAUUUGGAAUUUUUAGGAGUAGGUAAAUGUCUGGAUGGGGAUGUUACGGGAUAAGCUGAAAUUAGAGCUUACCAUGAUGUUUUAGCCUAAUUAAUGACAGGGAAGUCAGAAGGAGGCUAGAUGCCUGCUUAACAACAACAACAACAACAAAAAUCACAUAAUUCUUUUACUUGCUCCUUUGUAGGCAGGCAUCUUUAUUUUCUUAGAAAUAAGUAAAUGUCAUUUGUAGAGGCUAGAGGUUAGUGUUAUUAAUAAGAUAUCUAGUUCAGUCAUAUUACCUAGGCAACAGGUAAUGUUUUAGAUAGUGAAUGGUGAGUUAUUUGAUCUCAAAGAAAUCAAUAUGUGAAAUAGGAUGUACAUAACUUCAGAAGUUGACUUGUGAAGUCCCUAUUUUCUUUGGCUGGUCAUUAGGCUGCUAAGUAGAAUGACUGACUUUUGUAUGGUUUUCUUCCACAAUAGUGCUUUUUCUUUCGGUUCCCUACCUAUGAACUUUUCCUGAACUUUCCUACAAGUUUAAAAAGUUGUUAUGGCCUCUCUAUACAGUAGACAUCCAAUUCUUUGUUAACUGGAAAAAAGUUUCAGAAGUUUAAAUUUGAAGUAACAGGAAUUGGUCCAAAAUAUUUGUUGUUGCUCAUGUUUUAAAUAAGCGACAUUGGAUUAUAUCAGCACUGGGAUAAUUCCCAUUAGGUAUUAUGACUGCAAUUUACAUGCAAUUGGAAAUUAGUGAUUGAGAGGGAAACAGAUUGCCAAAUUAUCUUCCAAAAAGGUACUCCCCACUCCAUAUCCUUGCUAAUAACAAGUAUUAUAAUUAUUUAAAGUCAUUGCCAACUUGAUAGGCAAAAUAUUGUCUUGUUCUAAUGUUCAUUUCUUCUAUUGUGAAGGCGAACUUUUUUUUUCCAUGUUUCUUGAUCCUAUCUGUUGAUGAGGGCUGGAAGUUCAAGAAAGUAUAAAUUUAAAUUAUUUUAACCUGAAAAAUAAAGCCAGAGAACUUGAUUGAAAAGCACCCCAAAGACUGUGUUGAAAUCUGCAUUGCAAAUACUGAUGGAAACUUAUCCUUGUUUUCUUUGUUUUAUGCAUUACUUUACCAUCUUGCCAUAGUCAUUAGCUUUGCACCUAUUUAGGUUACAGCAUAAAAUCUAGGAACUCCACUUUGAAGGGAUCAUGGUUAUUCUUAAUUAGAAAUUGUCAAUUUAGCCUUAAGUAUUUUAUUUUUUGAAAUGUUUUAUGAUAAUGUGAAGUAAACCAUGCCAUUAUUUCUCAUUUUUCCCUUGGUUAACAAAUUAGGAUAUACAAAUCUUCAAAUUACCUUUAAGGCUUGUAAACAUUCAAAUCUUUUAUCCGUUAGUCAAGUUAUUUCAUAAACCCAACAUUGCCUCUGAAAUGGCUUUACACACAAAGAGGAUUUUACCAUAAAAUGCUUGUGGUGUUUCAUUCUCUUCUGAUUUUUUGUAGGGGAAGGGGGUUGGAGAGUAGGCAGAGUAUAAAUUAAUUUGGAUGGUGUUGGUUUCAAAGUAGCAUUCCAUGUAAUUCUGCAGAAAGUGUGAUAAAUAAGAAAAUGGGCCAGGCAUGGUGGCUCAUGCCAUAAUCCCAGCACUUUGGGAGGCCAAGGUGGGCAGAUCACCUGAGAUUGGGAGUUUGAGACCACCCUGGCCAACAUGGUGAAACCCUGUCUCUACUAAAAAUACAAAAAUUAACCGGGUGUGGUGGCACAUGCCUGUGGUCUCAGCUACUGGGGAGACUGAGGCAUGAGAAUCGCUUGAACACAGGAGGUGGAGGUUGUAGUGGGCCAAGAUUAAGCCACUGCACUCCAGCCUGGGCAACAGAGUGAGACUCUGUCUCAAAAAAUAAAAAAUAAAAAAAAUACAUAAUAAAACAAAGUUCAACAUUUGGGAAAUACCAGGUGAAUUAUAGUGUUACCCAUACAGUAGAAUACAAUGUGGUCAUUAAAAAACAUUAAAGGGGCUGGCCACUGUGGCUUACGCCUGUAAUCCCAGCACUUUGAGAGGCUGAGGUAGGCGGAUCAUUUGAGAUCAGGAGUUCGAGACCAGCCUGGCCAAGCUGGUGAAACCCCGUCUCUACUAAAAAUACAAAAAUUAGUCACUCGUAGUGGUGGACACCUGUAAUCCCAGCUACUCUGGAGGCUGAAGCAGGAGAAUCACUUGAACCUGGGAGGUGGAGCUUGCAGUGAGCUGCCAAGAUUGUGCCACUGCACUCCAGCCUGGGUGACAGAGUAAGACUAUGUCUCUAAAAAAAAAAAAAAGAAAAGAAAAAAAGCACUAAAGGGCAUUUCAUGACAGAAAGGUAUUCAUUAUAUAUAAGGAUAAUAGCAAGUGACAAAAUGCAGAACAUACAAUUUUACAGCAGGUGUUUUUUUUUUUUUUUCUUUUGAGAGCAUGGACAUAGACAAAUGGCUGGAAGGAAAUACACCAGUAUGUUUUAAUGACUAUCUUGAGUGGUUUUUAAAAUUUUCUGAAUUUUCCAAAUUAACAAAAACACAUUCUAGUCUGUUGAAUAGGAAAAAAAUACUACUUAAAAAAAUAAGGAAAAGUUGUAUGCCAUUUUAGAAACAAAAUUGUACUUAAAUCUCUGAAUUUUCUAGGCAGUUAAAUUUUUGAGCUCUUCUGUGGACUGUUUCUAAAUAAAAAUGAGUAGAUCCAUUAACAAUUGAUCAGUUUAUACAAGUGAUAAAUAGCAAGGUGAAUGUUUCCCAUACAUAUCUCAUUUCCCAUACUCAGGAUGUGCUUGCAUAAGUAGGAAUUGAGAGCAAAAGAAAUGGUAGGCUGUUGGGUCAUGGGCAAGAGACGAUUUAGUUGGCCAAAGAAGCAUAUUUUCUUAAGCAAAUGUUGGCCAAGAUGUUACUUUAUGUUUUCGGGCUGUCUUCACUGUAGUUGGAGAACUGUGAACUCUUGGUAUUAAGUACUCAGUAGGAGCAAAGAACCAUUUGGAAUGUCUGUCAAUCUUAAAUAGAACUGCAGCUGUUUGGCUGAGAGGUGAAAUGGACCUGGAUUUCUUUUUUUUGGCGGGGGGGCUUUGAAAGUAGUUUUUGUAUAACAAAGAGGUGAUGAGAACUAAAGUGAUUACAAAAGUGUUCAUAGGAGUUCAGUUUCUUUCCAGGCUUUGGGUUUAAGAAUGACUGUUUCUGCCCAUGGGGAAAUAAAUUGGCAUUUUUCUGCUUUCGUUUGUUUUUUAGUUAUUGAUGUUCUAGAAAUUUCAACAAAAUAAGGAGUGUUUUUGUAUUUCAAAUGUAGUGCCCGUUUCUUUAUUUCUUUCUGGUACUUUCCACUGGUUUGUGUUGAUAAUAUGAUCUGGAAGGUAGCGAUAAUGCAUGGGAAUUUAUAAAUGAUCACAAAAUACUUUGUCACAGGAAAUCUGGAGAAAUAAUGACUUUGGCAUAUGUAUAAGAGAAGUAUCUCUAACUGUUAAGUCUAAACUAAAAGCUUGUUACUUUUCGGUUUGGUAUAACCAAAAAAAAUUUGAAAAAUAAAAUAGAAGUAAUGAUUUGUUUUCUCAGGUGUAGUUGUAUUUGACUGACUCUAUUGUAGGAGGACACGUUUAAGACUGAAUGGUUGGAUAACGGUAAAGACGUCCUUUCAAUGGAGAGUUGAAUCUGAUAGGUUGAAGUUUUGGAUAUUGAAUGAAAAGAGAAAAGAGAGCCGGACAAGCUGAAAAUUCCUGUAGUUCCAACUACUGGGGAGGCUGAGGUGGGAGGAUCACCUGAGCCCAGGAGUUUGAGACUGCAGUGAGCUAUGAUCAUGCCACUGCGUUCCAGUCUGGAUGACAGAGUGAGACCCUGUGUCAAAAAAUAAGUAAAUAAAAAGAGGAAAGAGCUAAAA